UCAGGACUCAGGAUGCAAGACCCUGGUCAUCUCCAAGGCCCUCCCCUGGCCCUGGACCCUCCAAGGAGACAGCGGCAGGAGCGCACGGUCUACACUGAAAGCCAGCAGAAAGUGCUAGAAUUUUACUUUCAGAAGGACCAGUACCCGAACUACGACCAGCGACUGAAUCUGGCGGAGAUGCUCAGCCUCAGGGAGCAACAGCUGCAGGUGUGGUUCAAGAAUCGCCGCGCCAAACUAGCUCGGGAGCGGCGGCUCCAGCAGCAGCCCCAGCGCGUCCCUGGGCAGAGAGGCCGAGGAGCCCGCGCUGCGCCCCUAGUCCCUGUAGCCGCUGCCUCCUUCCCUGGGGGUCCUGAGUUCCCGCAGGGCAGGGGUUCCUGGAUCUCCCCUCAGCCGGGCCCCUGGGGAGUCCUCCCAGCAGCAGAACCGAAGAUCUACAGCCUCCCCCGGACCUGGGGUGGCCCUGAGUGUGGAACACAGGAGGGCCUCAAGGCUGUCCCGGCUCCAGGCCCUGGCCCAAUCCCAGCCCCUAUCCCAGGCCCAGCCCAGAUCCCAGGCCCAGUCCCAGGCCCAGCCCCGAAUUUAGGCCCAAUGUCAGGCCCACUGUCAGUCUCGAUCCCCGGUCCAAUACCAGCCCCCAUCUCUUGCCCAGGCCCAAUCCCAGACCCAGUCCUAGGCCGAACCCUGAUGCCAGGCCCAGGAUCACUCCCAACCCCAGCCCCAGGCGCCUUGUGGCCUCAGAGCCCCUAUGCCUCCAACUUGUCGCCAGACACCCAGUUAUACCCUGACUUCACCAAGCUGCUCCCGCUCCUAGACCGGUUCGAGGAAUCCUCACUCUCCACCACGACGUCUCAGUACAAAGAGGAGGAUGGCUUCGUGGACAAAAAUCACUCAGUCCCCAGGUCAUUACUGGAUUUAUAGGGGGCCUGUGCCUGCAAAGUUCUUCAGAUCCCAGAGGGCCUGGAGUGGCUGAUCUACACUGCUGGUGACUUUCUGCAGUGAAUGCAUCACCCUUUACCCACCCUGCUGCAGGUGGACAUUUGCUGUCUUCACUGUGCAGCCAUCACAGGUGGCUCUGCUGUGAAUGUGCCUGCCUGUCAUUUGAAUUGAGCCUGAGCGUUUCUCUGCUG